GGAAAAAUGCUUUUUUUCUCAUCGCAGUCUAGUCAAAUAUACUUAUAUUUUAUAAAAUUUCCUCGCAAACUGCCUUUCAAUAAAAUCUAAAGUUAAGUAGUAAAGUUCCAACCACAAGAAAACUCAUUCCUGAUAAUAUUUGAAUGUGGCCUCAUCUGGCAAAGCUAUUUAAGCAGGGCUCUGCUGCAGGAGUGGGUUCGGUAACACUAGAAUAAGGGCUCCUGGGGAAGAUGGGCUCUGUUCAGCUCCAUGACUGCAGAGGGAUGGAAAGGGGAAGGCUGUGUGAGGAGGUGUGAUUAGGGGGCUUCUUUGAGAAACUGAAAAUGAUUAAAGAAGGUAGGAGCGUGAGAAUUCUUAUUAUGUUUAACCCAUAGCCAACAUCAUGAGCAUAAGAAUUAAAGGAAGUCACUUGGUUUUUUAUUCUUGUUUUUGAGGGAACAGAAAGUCUUAACCAAAGAGAAAUUUCUUUGUGUGUGUGUGUGUGUGUGUGUGUGUGUGUGUGUGUGUGUUUUCUGAUAAUAAAAUAAAUGGUAAUACUUUUUUCAAGGUUUAAAAAAAGAGAGAGAGAAGGAAUGGAAAAGUUUAAAGAAGAAAAUAGAAAUCACCACUCAUCUCAAUAUUCAAAUAUUCCCACCACUAGAAUUGUGGGUUUUUCUUUUACUCAUACCUAUAUUAAAUACAAGUGUUAUCCUGUAUCUACAGUUUAGCAAAUCUAUGGUUGAUUCUAGUCACCAAAUAUUUGAGACAAAAAGAAAAUGUACAGUUGUAUGUAAUUGCCUUUUUAAUUUAACAUUCUAUCGCAAGCAUUUAUCCCUCACUUCCCCCAUCCACCUUCCCUGCAACAGGGAUUUUUGAAGAAAGCCAGCCUGUGCAUCUCUCCCCGCUCUGUCCCUGGAGACAGGGAUGUUGUCAUAGCCUAUGAGAGCAGAAGUUAGGGAGAGCUGCCACACGGCGGCGCUGUGGUGCAGGAAAAAAGCCCGAGGGCUGGUCCAGAGUCAGAGACCUGCAUUCGGCUUGGGCUCUAUCCUUCACUCGCGGUGAAAUUCAGAGCAAUUUCCUCCCUCUCUCAAUCCCAGCGUUUUUAAAUCCAUAAAUUGAGGGAAAUGGAGGAGGUGCGGUCAGGAAGUUUGUGAGCCUGGGUCAGCUGCUCUUGACUGAGACGACUUGGGCGAUUCUCUUUUAACUUCCAAGUUCUCUUCCAGUCUGAAACAUUCUAUGAUUAUUUGCGAUUUCAGACACGAAACUCAGGAAACACCAUUUGUAAGCAAUGAUUGGUAAUGCAAAUUGAGAACCAUUUUUCUUUCUUUCUCUUUAUUAAGAGACGAGGUCUCGCUAUGUUGCCCAGGCAGGCCUGGAACUCCUGGCCUCAAGUGAUCCACCUGCCUCAGGCUCCCAAGUAGCUGGGACUACAGGUACGGGCCACUCUGCCUGGUUGGGAAUCAUUUUUCUAAGUUGAAAUGAAGUUCCUGAGACAAUCCUGCAAGGUUACACCAUGUUAGUUCUGUUUUGUGGACCUGGCAAACCAUGCAUUCUGCAUGUAUAAUACACCAGGUAUUUUCAUUAGAGCAUUCCUUUGAGAGAGGUAGGGAGGUGACAUUUCCACUUUGCAGAGGAGUAGACUGAGGCUCAGAGAGGUUAAACGACUUGUCUAAUGUCUCAUGAAUCCAAGAGCUCUAACUUUUCAAUAAUUACUCCUUCUGCUACCAUAUAUUUCAAACCACUCAGAUGAGAGUAAUAGUCCUUUAAAUUAUUAGAAAAGGCUGCAGAAGCAAUGUUUUAAAAAAAUUGGGGUGAUUCAGCUUAGAGAAGAGAAGGCCAUGGGGGAUGCACGUAGGCAUGAAGUUUCUGCGGCUCAGUUGCACAUCUCAGCACGUCUUUCAUUCAAACUGGACCUGAAAUCUUCUCCCAGGGUGUCCUACUUUCGUGGACAAAAAAGUUUAAGGCACGAGGAGUUCAGGACACGGAUGUGGUGAGCCGUCUGACCAAAGCCAUGAGAAGACACAAGGACAUGGACGUGGACAUCCUGGCCCUGGUCAAUGACACCGUGGGGACCAUGAUGACCUGUGCCUAUGACGACCCCUACUGCGAAGUUGGUGUCAUCAUCGGAACUGGCACCAAUGCGUGUUACAUGGAGGACAUGAGCAACAUUGACCUGGUGGAGGGCGACGAGGGCAGGAUGUGCAUCAACACAGAGUGGGGGGCCUUCGGGGACGACGGGGCCCUGGAGGACAUUCGCACUGAGUUCGACAGGGAGCUGGACCUCGGCUCUCUCAACCCAGGAAAGCAACUGUUCGAGAAGAUGAUCAGUGGCCUGUACCUGGGGGAGCUUGUCAGGCUUAUCUUGCUGAAGAUGGCCAAGGCUGGCCUCCUGUUUGGUGGUGAGAAAUCUUCUGCUCUCCACACUAAGGGCAAGAUCGAAACACGGCACGUGGCUGCCAUGGAGAAGUAUAAAGAAGGCCUUGCUAAUACAAGAGAGAUCCUGGUGGACCUGGGUCUGGAACCGUCUGAGGCUGACUGCAUUGCCGUCCAGCAUGUCUGUACCAUCGUCUCCUUCCGCUCGGCCAAUCUCUGUGCAGCAGCUCUGGCGGCCAUCCUGACACGCCUCCGGGAGAACAAGAAGGUGGAACGGCUCCGGACCACAGUGGGCAUGGACGGCACCCUCUACAAGAUACACCCUCAGUACCCAAAACGCCUGCACAAGGUGGUGAGGAAACUGGUCCCAAGCUGUGAUGUCCGCUUCCUCCUGUCAGAGAGUGGCAGCACCAAGGGGGCCGCCAUGGUGACCGCGGUGGCCUCCCGCGUGCAGGCCCAGCGGAAGCAGAUCGACAGGGUGCUGGCUUUGUUCCAGCUGACCCGAGAGCAGCUCGUGGACGUGCAGGCCAAGAUGCGGGCUGAGCUGGAGUAUGGGCUGAAGAAGAAGAGCCACGGGCUGGCCACGGUCAGGAUGCUGCCCACCUACGUCUGCGGGCUGCCGGACGGCACAGAGAAAGGAAAGUUUCUCGCCCUGGAUCUUGGGGGAACCAACUUCCGGGUCCUCCUGGUGAAGAUCAGAAGUGGACGGAGGUCAGUGCGAAUGUACAACAAGAUCUUCGCCAUCCCCCUGGAGAUCAUGCAGGGCACUGGUGAGGAGCUCUUUGAUCACAUUGUGCAGUGCAUCGCCGACUUCCUGGACUACAUGGGCCUCAAGGGAGCCUCCCUACCUUUGGGCUUCACAUUCUCAUUUCCCUGCAGGCAGAUGAGCAUUGACAAGGGAACACUCAUAGGGUGGACCAAAGGUUUCAAGGCCACUGACUGUGAAGGGGAGGACGUGGUGGACAUGCUCAGGGAAGCCAUCAAGAGGAGAAACGAGUUUGACCUGGACAUUGUUGCAGUCGUGAAUGAUACAGUGGGGACCAUGAUGACCUGUGGCUAUGAAGAUCCUAAUUGUGAGAUUGGCCUGAUUGCAGGAACAGGCAGCAACAUGUGCUACAUGGAGGACAUGAGGAACAUCGAGAUGGUGGAGGGGGGUGAAGGGAAGAUGUGCAUCAAUACAGAGUGGGGAGGAUUUGGAGACAAUGGCUGCAUAGAUGACAUCUGGACCCGAUACGACACGGAGGUGGAUGAGGGGUCCUUGAAUCCUGGCAAGCAGAGAUACGAGAAAAUGACCAGUGGGAUGUACUUGGGGGAGAUUGUGCGGCAGAUCCUGAUCGACCUGACCAAGCAGGGUCUCCUCUUCCGAGGGCAGAUUUCAGAGCGUCUCCGGACCAGGGGCAUCUUCGAAACCAAGUUCCUGUCCCAGAUCGAAAGCGAUCGGCUGGCCCUUCUCCAGGUCAGGAGGAUUCUGCAGCAGCUGGGCCUGGACAGCACGUGUGAGGACAGCAUCGUGGUGAAGGAGGUGUGCGGAGCCGUGUCCCGGCGGGCGGCCCAGCUCUGCGGUGCUGGCCUGGCCGCUAUAGUGGAAAAAAGGAGAGAAGACCAGGGGCUAGAGCACCUGAGGAUCACUGUGGGUGUGGACGGCACCCUGUACAAGCUGCACCCUCACUUUUCUAGAAUAUUGCAGGAAACUGUGAAGGAACUAGCCCCUCGAUGUGAUGUGACAUUCAUGCUGUCAGAAGAUGGCAGUGGAAAAGGGGCAGCACUGAUCACUGCUGUGGCCAAGAGGUUACAGCAGGCACAGAAGGAGAACUAGGAACCCCUGGGAUUGGACCUGAUGCAUCUUGGAUACUGAACAGCUUUUCCUCUGGCAGAUCAGUUGGUCAGAGACCAAUGGGCACCCUCCUGGCUGACCUCACCUUCUGGAUGGCCGAAAGAGAACCCCAGGUUCUCGGGUACUCUUAGUAUCUUGUACUGGAUUUGCAGUGACAUUACAUGACAUCUCUAUUUGGUAUAUUUGGGCCAAAAUGGGCCAACUUAUGAAAUCAAAGUGUCUGUCCUGAGAGAUCCCCUUUCAACACAUUGUUCAGGUGAGGCUUGAGCUGUCAAUUCUCUAUGGCUUUCAGUCUUGUGGCUGCGGGACUUGGAAAUAUAUAGAAUCUGCCCAUGUGGCUGGCAGGCUGUUUCCCCAUUGGGAUGCUUAAGCCAUCUCUUAUAGGGGAUUGGACCCUGUACUUGUGGAUGAACAUUGGAGAGCAAGAGGAACUCACGUUAUGAACUAGGGGGAUCUCAUCUAACUUGUCCUUAACUUGCCAUGUUGACUUCAAACCUAUUAAGAGAACAAAGACUUUGAAGUAUCCAGCCCCAGGGUGCAGAGAGGUUGAUUGCCAGGGAGCACUGCAGGAAUCAUUGCAUGCUUAAAGCGAGUUAUGUCAGCACCCUGUAGGAUUUUGUUCCUUAUUAAGUGUGUGCCAUGUGGUGGGGUGCUGUCUGGGGCAUCUGUUUUUCAUUUUGCCUGUGGUUUGUGUUGCAGGUGUUGAUAGUUGUUUUAAGGAUUGUUAGGUAUAGGAAAUCCAGUAAAUUAAUAAAAAAAUUUUGAUUUUCCAAUAAA